UCUGGCAAUUUAGUUCAUUUACGUUUAUUAUAGUUAUUUACAUAUAUAUGAUGGUUAUUUAUAUAUGUGUCUACAUAAUUAGUUUUUAUCAAGAUGGGGUCUUGCCCUGUUGCCCAGGAUGGUCUCGAACUCCUGGGCUCGAGUAACCCUUCUGCCUGGGCCUCCUAAAGUGCUGGGAUUACAGGCGUGAGCCACUGCGCCCAGCCUAUUGUGGUUAUCAAUGCAUUUAUUCUUACCAUUUUAUGGUAUCUUAUACUUUCUGUUUAUCCUCUUUAUUUUAAAUUUUGUAAUAGCUUUAUUGAGGUGUACAUGACAUACAAUAACUGCACUUGUUUAAAGUUUUUUUUUUUUUUUUUUUUUUUUGAGACAGAGUCUUGCACUGUCGCCCAGGCUGGAGUGCAGUGGCGCAAUCUCGGCUCACUGCAAGCUCCACCUCCCGGGUUCACACCAUUCUCCUGCCUCAGCCUCCUGAGUAGCUGGGACUACAGCCACCCGCCACCACGCCUGGCUAAUUUUUUGUACUUUUAGUAGAGACAGGGUUUCACCAUGUUAGCCAGGAUGGUCUCGAUCUCCUGACCUCGUGAUCCACCCGCCUCGGCCUUCCACUAAGUGCUGGGAUUACAGGCAUGAGCCACCGCACCCAGCCUUAAAGUUAAAUUUAAUAAGUUGUGACAUAUGUUUACACCCAUAGAACUCACCACAAUCAAAACAUAAUAUCCUAAAAAUUUCACACCUAAACAUUUCCACCUUCCCCUUUGUAAUACUUCUCCCUGCCUCAGUUUCCUCACCCUAUCCCUGGGCAACCACUAAUUUGCUUUCUGUCACUAGGUAAGUUAGCAUUUUCUAGAAUUUUAUGUAAAUGGAAUCAACGGUAUAUAAUUUGGAGGGGGUAGUUUCUUUAAUCAUAAUUAUUUUGAAAUUCAUUCUGUCUUCUAAAGAUUGGGCAUCUCUAAUUCCAAAGUCUGAAACUUCUGGAGCACCAUAAGUGGACAAUUCCACAUCUGACCUCAUGUGACAGGUUGCAGUCAAAACUUUGUUUCAUGCACAAAAUUAUUUAAAAUACUAUGUAAAAUUGCCAUCAGGCUGUUUGUAUAAGGUGUAGAUGAAACACACAAAUUUCAUAGUUAGACUUGGAGCCCUUCCCAAGAUACCCCAUUAUAUAUAUGCAAUUAUUUGAAAUUUGAAACACUUCUGGUUCUAAGCAUUUCAGAUAAGGGAUAUUCAGCCUGUAUUUUAUUUUUCUUUUAUUUGUGUGUUUUUUGUUUUUGUUUUUGAGAAGGAGUCUCACUGUGUUGCCCCGGCUGGAAUGCAGCGGUGCAAUCCUGGCCCACUGCAACCUCUGCCUCCUGGGUUCAAGUGAUUCUCAGGCCUCAGCCUCCUGGGUAGCUGGGACUACACGUGAGCACCACCACGCCCAGCUAAUUUUUAUAUUUUUAGUAGAGAUGAGGUUUCAGCAUGUUGGCCAGGCUGGUCUUGAACUCCUGACCUUAGAUGAUUCGCUCGCCUCAGCCUCCCAGAGUACUGGGAUUACAGGCAUGAGCCACCACACCUAGCCUACAUGUAUUUUCUCAUCCUCUUUUUUUUUUCCCCGUUUCUAGUUAUAUAUAUUUUCUUAUUAUUCAUUUUGUUUUUUUCUGCUGGUUUGGGAGUUAGACGUGCUAUGCUUUUAGAGGUUAUUCUUGAAUUUUUUUUUUUUUUUUUUUGAGACACUAGCCUGUUGCCGAGGCUAGAAUGCAGUGAGUGGCGCAAUCUCGGCUCACUGCAAGCUCCGCCUCCCGGGUUCACGCCAUUCUCCUGCCUCAGCCUCCUGAGUAGCUGGGACUACAGGCACCUGCCACCAUGCCCAGCUAAAUUUUUUUGUAUUUUUAGUAGAGACGGGGUUUCACUGUGUUAGCCAGGAUGGUCUCGAUCUCCUGACCUCGUGAUCUGCCCACCUCAGCCUCCCAAAGUGCUGGAAUUACAGGCGUGAACCACCGCACCCAGCCAAAUUUUUUUUUGUUAACCUGUAAACUAACUUGUAUACCUAAUCAGAAUAGUCUAAAAUUAGUUGAAUCAAUGUUCUGAGGAAAACCCUUGAGAAAAUAAAGUUAGAAUUUCAAGUGUCAGAAUCUUUUUGACAUUGAGAGUUUGUGGCUUUGUAGUGUAGAAGAAUAAUUCACAGACACUAUUUCACUUGUGUAACAAGGGAGACAGAUUUUCAGAUUAAUUUCCAACCGAGCAAAAGCAGGAUUUAUAUAGGAGAAAGAGGAACAAGGAGAGAGGGCAAAACCACAGAACAGUGGAUUCUGUUUGCCCGUUUUUCUGUGUAAACUCUGAUAUUAACUCUCCUUGAGUAUGCCACCCAGGGUUGGUGGAUGCUCUAGAAAACACGAUAGGCCCUCUGCCAGUAAGGGUUUUCAGCAACUCCAGAUUCAGCCAGUCUAAAUAUACCCUUUCCAUCAUCAGCAUUUCUCAGCCUUCAUCUUUUGGUCAAAACAAGCUUGUAAAGGAGUGGGUUUAUUCUCAUGAGCUUCAGCCUCUUUGAUGUGGGAUAAGGCCAUCUGUUGUCUUAUGGUGAUCUGAAGGUAUUAGGGGGAAGUUCAUCUAUACCUGAUGUCAUGAUUGACCUGUGAACUCUUUUUCUUUUUUUCUUUUUUUAGAUGGAGUCUUGCUCUGUUGCCCAGGCUGGAGUGCAGUGGUGCAAUCUCAUCUCACUGCAACCUCCGCCUCCCUGGUUCAAGCAGUUCUCCUCAGCCUCCCAAGUAGCUGGGAUUACAGGGCACCCACCACAGAUGAGGACAAGAAGGCAGCCGAGAAGAAACGGGAGGACAAAGCUAAGAAGAAGCACGACAGGAAAUCCAAGCGCCUGGAUGAGGAGGAGGAGGACAAUGAAGGCGGGGAGUGGGAAAGGGUCCGGGGCGGAGUGCCGUUGGUUAAGGAGAAGCCAAAAAUGUUUGCCAAGGGAACUGAGAUCACCCAUGCUGUUGUUAUCAAGAAACUGAAUGAGAUCCUACAGGCACGAGGCAAGAAGGGAACUGAUCGUGCUGCCCAGAUUGAGCUGCUGCAACUGCUGGUUCAGAUUGCAGCGGAAAACAACCUGGGAGAGGGCGUCAUUGUCAAGAUCAAGUUCAAUAUCAUCGCCUCUCUCUAUGACUACAACCCCAACCUGGCAACCUACAUGAAGCCAGAGAUGUGGGGGAAGUGCCUGGACUGCAUCAAUGAGCUGAUGGAUAUCCUGUUUGCAAAUCCCAACAUUUUUGUUGGAGAGAAUAUUCUGGAAGAGAGUGAGAACCUGCACAACGCUGACCAGCCACUGCGUGUCCGUGGCUGCAUCCUAACUCUGGUGGAACGAAUGGAUGAAGAAUUUACCAAAAUAAUGCAAAAUACUGACCCUCACUCCCAAGAGUACGUGGAGCACUUGAAGGAUGAGGCCCAGGUGUGUGCCAUCAUCGAGCGUGUGCAGCGCUACCUGGAGGAGAAGGGCACUACCGAGGAGGUCUGCCGCAUCUACCUGCUGCGCAUCCUGCACACCUACUACAAGUUUGAUUACAAGGCCCAUCAGCGACAGCUGACCCCGCCUGAGGGCUCCUCAAAGUCUGAGCAAGACCAGGCAGAAAAUGAGGGCGAGGACUCGGCUGUGUUGAUGGAGAGACUGUGCAAGUACAUCUACGCCAAGGACCGCACAGACCGGAUCCGCACAUGUGCCAUCCUCUGCCACAUCUACCACCAUGCUCUGCACUCGCGCUGGUACCAGGCCCGCGACCUCAUGCUCAUGAGCCACUUGCAGGACAACAUUCAGCAUGCAGACCCGCCAGUGCAGAUCCUUUACAACCGCACCAUGGUGCAGCUGGGCAUCUGUGCCUUCCGCCAAGGCCUGACCAAGGACGCACACAACGCCCUGCUGGACAUCCAGUCGAGUGGCCGAGCCAAGGAGCUUCUGGGCCAGGGCCUGCUGCUGCGCAGCCUGCAGGAGCGCAACCAGGAGCAGGAGAAGGUGGAGCGGCGCCGUCAGGUCCCCUUCCACCUGCACAUCAACCUGGAGCUGCUGGAGUGUGUCUACCUGGUGUCUGCCAUGCUCCUGGAGAUCCCCUACAUGGCCGCCCAUGAGAGCGAUGCCCGCCGACGCAUGAUCAGCAAGCAGUUCCACCACCAGCUGCGCGUGGGCGAGCGACAGCCCCUGCUGGGUCCCCCUGAGUCCAUGCGGGAACAUGUGGUCGCUGCCUCCAAGGCCAUGAAGAUGGGUGACUGGAAGACCUGUCACAGUUUUAUCAUCAAUGAGAAGAUGAAUGGGAAAGUGUGGGACCUUUUCCCCGAGGCUGACAAAGUCCGCACCAUGCUGGUUAGGAAGAUCCAGGAAGAGUCACUGAGGACCUACCUCUUCACCUACAGCAGUGUCUAUGACUCCAUCAGCAUGGAGACGCUGUCAGACAUGUUUGAGCUGGAUCUGCCCACUGUGCACUCCAUCAUCAGCAAAAUGAUCAUUAAUGAGGAGCUGAUGGCCUCCCUGGACCAGCCAACACAGACAGUGGUGAUGCACCGCACUGAGCCCACUGCCCAGCAGAACCUGGCUCUGCAGCUGGCCGAGAAGCUGGGCAGCCUGGUGGAGAACAACGAACGGGUGUUUGACCACAAGCAGGGCACCUACGGGGGCUACUUCCGAGACCAGAAGGACGGCUACCGCAAAAACGAGGGCUACAUGCGCCGCGGUGGCUACCGCCAGCAGCAGUCUCAGACGGCCUACUGAGCUCUCCACUCUGUUUCCCGCCUGGGCCAUCCAACCUUGAAGUCCUAAACCACACCUCAGUCACUAAAGGUCUGUUUAAAGUUGUUCUGGUUGAUUGCUUGUUGCCACAAAGGUGUGUUGAGCCCAUUCAUUUGCUGAUUAUAUUUCUGAGCUGCUACCACAUGACAGACACAAGGCUCAGAUGAAGAGGUGAAUUGAACACGUUCCUGACCUCAAA